AGUCAAUCAGCGGCAGAGCUGAGAAGGGCACAGCCGCGCGGCGGAGGGCAGAGUCAGCCGAGCCGAGUCCAGCCGGACGAGCGGACCAGCGCAGGGCAGCCCAAGCAGCGCGCAGCGAACGCCCGCCGCCGCCCACACCCUCUGCGGUCCCCGCGGCGCCUGCCACCCUUCCCUCCUUCCCCGCGUCCCCGCCUCGCCGGCCAGUCAGCUUGCCGGGUUCGCUGCCCCGCGAAACCCCGAGGUCACCAGCCCGCGCCUCUGCUUCCCUGGGCCGCGCGCCGCCUCCACGCCCUCCUUCUCCCCUGGCCCGGCGCCUGGCACCGGGGACCGUUGCCUGACGCGAGGCCCAGCUCUACUUUUCGCCCCGCGUCUCCUCCGCCUGCUCGCCUCUUCCACCAACUCCAACUCCUUCUCCCUCCAGCUCCACUCGCUAGUCCCCGACUCCGCCAGCCCUCGGCCCGCUGCCGUAGCGCCGCUUCCCGUCCGGUCCCAAAGGUGGGAACGCGUCCGCCCCGGCCCGCACCAUGGCACGGUUCGGCUUGCCCGCGCUUCUCUGCACCCUGGCAGUGCUCAGCGCCGCGCUGCUGGCUGCCGAGCUCAAGUCGAAAAGUUGCUCGGAAGUGCGACGUCUUUACGUGUCCAAAGGCUUCAACAAGAACGAUGCCCCCCUCCACGAGAUCAACGGUGAUCAUUUGAAGAUCUGUCCCCAGGGUUCUACCUGCUGCUCUCAAGAGAUGGAGGAGAAGUACAGCCUGCAAAGUAAAGAUGAUUUCAAAAGUGUGGUCAGCGAACAGUGCAAUCAUUUGCAAGCUGUCUUUGCUUCACGUUACAAGAAGUUUGAUGAAUUCUUCAAAGAACUACUUGAAAAUGCAGAGAAAUCCCUGAAUGAUAUGUUUGUGAAGACAUAUGGCCAUUUAUACAUGCAAAAUUCUGAGCUAUUUAAAGAUCUCUUCGUAGAGUUGAAACGUUACUACGUGGUGGGAAAUGUGAACCUGGAAGAAAUGCUAAAUGACUUCUGGGCUCGCCUCCUGGAGCGGAUGUUCCGCCUGGUGAACUCCCAGUACCACUUUACAGAUGAGUAUCUGGAAUGUGUGAGCAAGUAUACGGAGCAGCUGAAGCCCUUCGGAGAUGUCCCUCGCAAAUUGAAGCUCCAGGUUACUCGUGCUUUUGUAGCAGCCCGUACUUUCGCUCAAGGCUUAGCGGUUGCGGGAGAUGUCGUGAGCAAGGUCUCCGUGGUAAACCCCACAGCCCAGUGUACCCAUGCCCUGUUGAAGAUGAUCUACUGCUCCCACUGCCGGGGUCUCGUGACUGUGAAGCCAUGUUACAACUACUGCUCAAACAUCAUGAGAGGCUGUUUGGCCAACCAAGGGGAUCUCGAUUUUGAAUGGAACAAUUUCAUAGAUGCUAUGCUGAUGGUGGCAGAGAGGCUAGAGGGUCCUUUCAACAUUGAAUCGGUCAUGGAUCCCAUCGAUGUGAAGAUUUCUGAUGCUAUUAUGAACAUGCAGGAUAAUAGUGUUCAAGUGUCUCAGAAGGUUUUCCAGGGAUGUGGACCCCCCAAGCCCCUCCCAGCUGGACGAAUUUCUCGUUCCAUCUCUGAAAGUGCCUUCAGUGCUCGCUUCAGACCACAUCACCCCGAGGAACGCCCAACCACAGCAGCUGGCACUAGUUUGGACCGACUGGUUACUGAUGUCAAGGAGAAACUGAAACAGGCCAAGAAAUUCUGGUCCUCCCUUCCGAGCAACGUUUGCAACGAUGAGAGGAUGGCUGCAGGAAACGGCAAUGAGGAUGACUGUUGGAAUGGGAAAGGCAAAAGCAGGUACCUGUUUGCAGUGACAGGAAAUGGAUUAGCCAACCAGGGCAACAACCCAGAGGUCCAGGUUGACACCAGCAAACCAGACAUACUGAUCCUUCGUCAAAUCAUGGCUCUUCGAGUGAUGACCAGCAAGAUGAAGAAUGCAUACAAUGGGAACGACGUGGACUUCUUUGAUAUCAGUGAUGAAAGUAGUGGAGAAGGAAGUGGAAGUGGCUGUGAGUAUCAGCAGUGCCCUUCAGAGUUUGACUACAAUGCCACUGACCAUGCUGGGAAGAGUGCCAAUGAGAAAGCCGACAGUGCUGGUGUCCGUCCUGGGGCACAGGCCUACCUCCUCACUGUCUUCUGCAUCUUGUUCCUGGUUAUGCAGAGAGAGUGGAGAUAAUUCUCAAACUCUGAGAAAAAGUGUUCAUCAAAAAGUUAAAAGGCACCAGUUAUCACUUUUCUACCAUCCUAGUGACUUUGCUUUUUAAAUGAAUGGACAACAAUGUACAGUUUUUACUAUGUGGCCACUGGUUUAAGAAGUGCUGACUUUGUUUUCUCAUUCAGUUUUGGGAGGAAAAGGGACUGUGCAUUGAGUUGGUUCCUGCUCCCCCAAACCAUGUUAAACGUGGCUAACAGUGUAGGUACAGAACUAUAGUUAGUUGUGCAUUUGUGAUUUUAUCACUCUAUUAUUUGUUUGUAUGUUUUUUUCUCAUUUCGUUUGUGGGUUUUUUUUUCCAACUGUGAUCUCGCCUUGUUUCUUACAAGCAAACCAGGGUCCCUUCUUGGCACGUAACAUGUACGUAUUUCUGAAAUAUUAAAUAGCUGUACAGAAGCAGGUUUUAUUUAUCAUGUUAUCUUAUUAAAAGAAAAAGCCCAAAAAGCAGUAAAAUUUCCAUUUCUCCCUGUUAUUUUAGUUGCCUUAUCUGGAGAGACGUGGAGGUGAUUUUCUUUUUUUUAAAUUAUUAUUAAGACAGAAUGUGAGGGCACAAGCAGGCUUCUGAGCCACUUGUCAGAUUGUAUUCAAAGCAUCAAUCCAAGAAGGAGGUUAUGUGUACUUCAUUUAUUGGUGAUAGUUGGAAGAGACUGCAGACUACUGCUUUGAAUGAGUUGAAUUACAUAAGCUAAGAUCACUAUAGGUCCAUUUCUUGAACCCACUUAUACAUAAAAUGUAACCCAUUUAGAAAAAGAUUCUGGAUAUCAUCCCCCUUGAAAGAUAGAAAGCAUUCAGGAUGUCCCAGUUAUCACAUGUUCACACUUGGGUUUAGGGGUGUUUUUUUUUAAAACCAGGCAGGUUAGCUAGCCCACCCUGUGCUAGUUUUCAUGUUCACACUGACCCUAUUUGAAUUAAUAUCCUUUGUUAGAGUGGUCGAGAUUUCAAACCCAAUUAUGUACAGGGAGCUGUCUGAGAGCUAGCCAGAACUGGGGUACAGCCUGGGCUCAGGGAAUAGCUGUCAACACUCGGGCAAAGUUUUUGUCUGUGCAUGUGUAUCUCCAUUUGUUUUGGGAUCCCAGUUUUUGUUUUAAGAGAGUAUAAGGUGUCUCAUUUGAGUCUUUUUCUUACCUAGCCCCCUCUUAUCAGUAAAACAAAGGACUUGCCAUGGUUCACAGCAAUGUGCUACGAUCCAAGAUAUCAGCCAAGGAGCCCACUUAGGGGAGAACUAGGUGUCCAGAUUUUUGUAUGUGUUGUUUUUCUUGGGGGAUGGGGUGGGGUGGGAGUAGGUAGAGCUGAGAAUACUACAUCUUAGUGGUGACCUUUAGCCACGUGGGUGAAGUGGCAAAGGCCAUGGCCAUAUCUGUUGUCCCAGGCCAAAGACUAACAACUGCCUUGGGAAUCCCUUCCUUGUGUCCUUACCAAAUGAUAGCUCAUAAAACUCUGAUAAUGUAACAAAUCACUUUCAAAGGAGUUCCCAGAAGUCUUCAGAAAGACUAAAAUUCUGUCUCUUCCUGCUUUAGACAGCCAUUAAGAUCCCAACUAAUUUUACCGAACCUAAAACCCACAAAGAGGUUGUUUGUGUUAUUGUUCAAUCUUCAGUUGUAAGAGUAAUUCUCUAUUUUUAUAUUGAAACAUAAUUACUUGAUAGCUCAGGGUCUACAUUUCAUUCAACUUUUUACACCAAAUUCUGCAGAGUGGUCAAAAUGGAAUAUUGGGGGCUGUUGUAAACAGAGGCUUAAUUUUAUUAGAAGUAGCCAGUUAUUUAUUAAAGCAUGAUGUUAAUAAAAUAGGCAUAUUCUGGCUGGUGUGUAUAAGUGGUUUUUUUUUUAAAACAAAUCAGAAGACAUAAAAUUGAAAAGGCACUCCAUUUAUAUAUAAGGGAAAAUAGAUUGUAAAUAGCUAAGGGGCCUUGUGAGAACUUGGAAAAUGUGCUGAUACUUAGUAACUACCUCAGUUGUGAGGAAUUUCCUUUUUAGCUUAGACUGCUAUUACUUUUACUUGGUAGAAAUGAAUCUGGUCUCCAAAAUAUGGCUCAGAGAGUUAUCCCCAUAGACCUUGUUAGAUUGUUUUUAAUUUAAAACCUUGAACUCUGCCCAGCUGUUUUCUUCCAGUCAAAUUCUCUAAACCAAUAACAUUUUCCAAAUUAAGUAUUCUUGAAGGUUCUUCUGAACUCUUACUGAUUUGUUUUCUUUCUUUGCAUUUUUUCCUGUUACUCUUUUAUUAUUUAAAUUGUCUCUUGCUUUUGAACUUCAACUAUGAAAUAAACAAAUCAUAGAUUUUUCCAUUCAGGUCUGACUGGAUAACUCUUGGCUUCUAAGCAGCUGGCAAGCUCACCCCCACUCCCCAAAAAAGAAGAAAGGCAAGUUGAAUAUUUUAAAACCUUAAGAGUUUGGAGUAUGAAGUAGAAUAAAAGCCUUGUUAGGAGAAGACCUGACUUUUCCAAAGUUAACAGCAUGUGAAGGGCUUGUGUUUUACAAAGUCAUUUAUAAAUUAUUUUUCUUUAAAACACAUCACCUACUCUGUACCUUAAAGAUUUUACAACUCUUAGAUUUAUAUUUUAUUUCAAAAAUCGUAACUAGCACCUGUUAUUUUGAUUAAAAGACACUGCGAAGAAUUGACGUAAAUUUCUAAAGUUUAGUUACUGAGUGUUCAAAACCUAACAGUUCACAUGAAGUAAAAAUUGUCAUUUGUGAUUACAGAAUCAAAAUAAAAAUAGGUAUGAAUGGUGCUA